AAGCAGAGAGACCCCAGCAGCAGCAGCAGCUGAUGAUGAAGAGAGAGGCAGUGGCAGAGGGGGGGCACCUUUUAUUUCUAUUUUUAAAGGGACAGGACACUAAUUCUACCCCACUUCAACCUUGAAUUCAGGGGGGUGGGGGGAAGGCGGCUGAGUUCCUUCCCCCACCCUCCAGCCCUGAGCCCUGAGAGGGGGAUUGAGCCUGAGAGAGGAGAAGGAGUUUCUUCUUCUUCGAAAACCCCCAUCCACGACUCCUACCCCCUCACCCCUCCAACUCGCCUCCCUCCCUCCACCCUCCUCCUCUUUGGCCGUGAGAGGAGGAGAGAAAGAAACCAAAAGCCUCUUAGCAACACAGACCCUUUGCUGCUGCUGUUGCUGCUGCUGCUGCUGUUGCUGCUGCUGCUGCUACUGCUGCUGCUGCUACUGCUGCUGCUUGGCCCUGGCUGGAGACAUCUCACUACACCCAGGAGCAGCCACUUCCCCAGCUCUCCUCCUCCUCCUUCGCCUCCUCCUCCUCCACUCCCCCCCUUUAUUACCCUUUGUGUCAUCCUCCACAGCUCCAGGGAAGGCACUCAAAAGUGGGGGGCAGGAAAGACAAUUAUCAACUUUCCAGUUUUCUAUGGAUAUGAAGAUUUACUCCUAGUCAUCAGUGGGACCCCCAUGAAGUCAGCCAGAAAGCCUAUAUCCAACUUAUGUACCUUUGCAAACUUGUCUGGAUUUUGACUGUAUGUGCAAAACAGAUUGUACUUAGCGAUUCAUUAAACAUCUUUUGAUCAUCUGCUGUCUGCCAGGCACUGUGCUAGGCAUCUGAAAAACAAAGAUGGUCCCUGCAGUUUAAUGUGAAGAGCUAUCUUAAUUGUAUUCCACAAGUGUAUUGGUCGUAUCUUUGUUUUGGUGUUUCUACCUAAAUAAAUUUUAUAUUAACUAAAUGGAUACUGUUAGGUGGAAAAAUGCAUGUUUAAGAAAGAUAUUGCUGUUAUUUUAUUAAAAUACAAAUAUAUAAAGAAAAAUUUUCCACUUAAUACUGUAUUCUAGGGAUUUAUAUUCUGUAUAUAGUUAACACAUUUUAGACAAUGAAAAUAGCCUAUGUGGUUGCCUUUGCUGGAUUUUUAUUGCUAACCGUAAUUCUUUUAAGAUGACCAACAAUGUUCAUUAAGUUAUCUCAUUAAAUUUUUCCAAAAAAAAAAAAACACCCCAAACCCUCUAAACUUAAAUCUUUUUCUCAAAAGUAACUUUUUUCUUUUUUAUCUCAUAUAACAGAUUAUCAUUCAUGAUUCAUUGGAAGACAUUGUACAUUUUCAUUUUGAGUUUUCAGAUAUUUUCUACCAAAUUUUAGCAAAUCUAACAGCAUGAUUUAAUUAUUCUGCAGUAAUUAGUGUGCACUAUUUAGGAGUUUUGGAAUUUUUAGUAUGUAGUAGAAAUAUCAUUGCAAAAUCCUCAUAAGAAACUUCCCAAUUCUAGUUCUAAGUCAGUUGUAAUUUUUAAUCUUUAUUAAGUGGUAUAAUCUCUAUAGCUUUAGUAAAAUGAUUUGGAAUUUUCUUAGUAGAUAGAUGUUUCAAAAACAAAGAAUCUUAUCUCAGUUCCUGUCAUGGCUUUCAUGUGUAAUCGAAAAGUAUAUUAGAAAAAGUACUGGAUUAAAUUUGCCUUUCUUAAAGUAUACCUUUUACAAAAGUAUUGAUUUGCAGUUAAAAAGAAGGUGGGGAUGCCUCUGCUGGUGCAGUAUCUUGUGAAGAUAAAUAGACUCCUGAGUGGUGAAUUCUGAUCUCUUUCACGUUCAUUCUUAACUUUCUAUUUUAGUAAUAAUCAUAGUUACCAUUGAUUAUAAGUACCCAGCACUGUGAUAAAUUGAAUUCACAUUACAUUUAUGACACUUUCUAAUUCAAAACACAGUCACAGUAGAGUUUUUAUCAAUCUGUACACUGGUAAGCGAUGGUAAAAUUAUGGCCCUGAUAGCUUCACAGACUAAUGGAAAAUUUCUGAAAGUUUACAAGUACAGAAAAACAAAGAAAAAAAACCCAGUCUUUUAUAAGGAAUGUAGAUACAGACCAUUGUACAAUUUAAAAUAUACAUAAUGUCAGUCUUUUCUUUGUAUGGCAAAAAUGACAUUUGGGAACUGCUCAUGGUGACUCAACGCUUGUAAUGUAAUCCCAGCUACUCGGAGGCUGAGGCGGGAGAAUUAUUUGAGCCCCAGAUUUUGAGGCUGCAGCGAACUAUGCAAUCCAGCCUAGGCCACAGAGCGGGACCUUGUCUCUAAAAAUAAAAAAUAAGGUCAGGUGGAAUAGCUCAAGCCUGUAAUUCCAACAACUGGGAGGUGAGGUAGGAGGAUUUAUCACUUGAGGCUAGUAGUUCAGGGUCAGCCUGUGCAAUGUAGUGAGAUCUGAUCCCUACAAAAUCAAAAUAGUAGCUGAGCUUGGUGUGGUGCACACUGUAGUCCCAGCUACUCAGGAGGCUGGAGAGGAUCUCUUGAACUCAGGUUGAGGCUGCAGUGAGCCAUGAUCAUGCCACUGGACUCUGUGCUGAGCAACAGAGUGAGACCCUGUCUCUAAAUAAAUAAAUAAACAAAUAAAAAAACAGUAAAAAAAAGUUCAGUUCAAUCCUUAUCUGUAUUAAACUUCCUUUAACUUGUGUGGAGUUACAUUUAAUAUUUUCUUAUAUGAAGUUCAAAGGUUAUAACAAUUUCUGAUCCAAUGAAUAUUUACUAUAAAAUUUUUAAUAUAAAUGUGUUGAUGGUGUAAAAGCCCAUAAAAAAUGGGAAGUUUAUAUUGUCUUGUGCUUUGGUGUAUGUAUACACAUUACCUUCUGGACUCUAUCAUACAUUUUCAUAAUUACUACAUUACAUAUAUAGGAUUAAGUUUAAUGUACUCUUUUUAGUACUAAAGUCAGAAAUAUUUUGGUAUAAGAAUGAUCAACUUGUUGGGUUCUCUAGGUGCCUAAAUUAUUUCAUAUUUAUACUUAAAAGCUACUGAAUUAAAAUACUUUUUAAUACAGUUCUCUUUGGGUAGUUGAGUUUUACAUCCUUUACUUUUAAGAGAAAAAAAAUUAAAAACUUUUUUUCCUGUUUUUAUUACUUAAGUAACUUUUGUGUCUCUUCUAAGUAAAUACAUGUUCAUAUUAUAAAUUUAUACAGGUUGAGUAUUCCUAAUCCAGAAUUCCAAAAUCCGAAAUGCUUAAAAAUCUGAAACUUUUUGAGCACUGACAUGAUGCUCAAAGAAAAUGCUCACUGAAGCAUUUUGGAUUUUGGAUUUUGAGGUUAGGGAUGUUCAAUAGAUAUAUAAGGCAAAUAUUCCCAAAUCUGUAAAAAUCCAAAAUUCUAAAUACUUCUGGUCCACAAAACCUUUUGAAUAAGGGAUAUCAACUUUUAUUGACUCUAUCGUCCUGCAAAUAUUAUGCCAGUACAUAAUGACCUGCAGAGUUUGGAAACAUUUUUAAAUGCUAAAGAAAUAUUCUUUAUCAUCUGUUAUAUAUUAGAAAAGUUUAUUGCAAAUGUUUUGUUGCUUAUAAGAAUAAUCCGAAUAAUCAGUAGUGUGAUCUUAAAUAAUUUCUUUAAACAACCCAAAGAUAAUUCAGUUAAAAGUAAAUAUUCUAACUCUAACACUUAGAGUAUUUCUGUUUGAGGUAUUUCUAUGUCAUGUAAGAUGUCAGAAGCUGGAAUGACUCACUGUAACUCACUAUAACUCUUCAAAGAGACAGUGAGAUCCAGGCUUAACUUAUAUUAUGGUAUAAUUUAUUCAAAGUUGGAUAUCACAAAUUUUGAUUUGUAUCCUUAUUUCAGUUGACCUAUAUAACCUUUUAUUAGAGAACCUGUAAUUAAGUUCAGUGUCAUUGAGUAGAUUAUUAGAAUACAUUGUUUUAAAGGACUAAUAUGAGUUAUGUAAAUCAGUCACCAACCUUGAAAUGGUGAAAAGUUUUUGUACACAUAUGCUUCACUGAAUUCUUCUGCUAACCAAUCAAGAUUCUAGCAAUGGGAGGAAAAUUUUCUGUGUGGUGCUAAUGUUAAAACUUAAGUUCAUGUGUAGCUUUUAAAAAAAAAAUUUAAUAUCUGUAUCUCAGAAGUUAGAAGUAAUCCCAAAGUGUUUUUUAAGAUUGACUGUGUGCUAAAUUAUACUUAGGGUUAUCCUUGUAUUCACAAUUACUGUUUUUUAUACACCAUGAGUCCAGAAGUAUCUACUAAUCUGUUGGCCAUCAACUAACUUAAUCCAUACAUUCUUAAUAUUAUUAGGAUCUAAAAAUAAUAAUUUAGACUGUAUAAGUACAUUUACUGAUGUUGGGGGAGGGAAAUAUUCCACAUUCAAUAAAAGCAAAUAUUGAUUUUUAAAUAGCUUUGUUACUUGGGAUAUACUGACCUAAAAAGAGUUCACUGUGUAAGAUAUAAAAUAUUCUUAUUUGAAAAGUUAUAAAGUAUCAUUAAUGAGUAUUAAAUAACAUAAAAAUAUUUAGGAAAUCAAAUACGUGCUCCUGUAAUAUUCAGAGGCUAUUUUUUUAGUGUUAUUCCAAAAUCAUUUUCCUUCUAUAUUUGUCACACUGGAGUUUCUGCUGAAGGAUUUCUUGGCCAUUUUAGACAAUGUAAUCUAGUUAAAAGGUUUGUUUAUGCUUCCCAUCUCUGUUCUGCUGAUGGUAUUAGAAUGCAGGCCAGAGCCAGACAUCUAACUGUUUAUAACAUUCAAACUUCAAUUAAAGCUACAGUGUUCAGUUUACUAUGUAUCAGAAAGCUCUUACUAGCUACAAAUAUCACUAAUAGUGAUGAGAGUGAUGUUGACUAGCUAUAAGCUUUCCUAAAUCAUACCACUCAUUAAGAAUACUUUUUUUAAAAUUUAGGUGUUAACCUUUAAUUCUUUCAUAGAAGUAUAAAAUUAAGCUUUUUUUUUUUACUAGAAGUAAUAUAGUCUUUUCCUUUAACACUUUUUAUAAUAAAACCUAACAGCAUAUAUUAUUGCAUGUAUUAUUUAAAUGGUCCACCUUAGUUGUUUUGAAAUUAAUGAAUUCUGUAGAAGGUGUUACUUUGCUAUUCAAUUUAUUCGAAUUUUCUUCCUAGCUUGAAAAAUAUAGCAAUAUGUUGCCCACUAGAAAAUAAACCUAACAGUCACAUUAGUCAGGUGUUCUUACAUGUAUGAAAGGAGUCUAGUCCCACAUAACACAGAUUCUAAUUUAACAUAUCGCUUUUCUAGGCUGCUGUUCUUAUUGUUUUAAGUAUUUUGGUAAAUUGUUUUAGAAGGGUUUUUUGUUUUUAAAAAUUAUUUAGAAUUCUUUGAAACCAUUUCUUCAACAGCUUCUGUUUUUGUACAGUUUACCUGGGCCAGUCAGAAAAGGAUUUGAAUUUUAUGUGUGUUUAAUUUUUCUAAUUAGUAGGCAAAUUUGCUAUGUUACAUUGGUUUCUUUUUUUACGAAACCAAAUUUUAGUUUUUAUUAAUUUUAGACCUUGAAUGACUAAAUCUACACAUUCUUUAUGUAUGUACAUGUAAUUUUUAUUGACAUCCAAGUUUAUAAGAGGUAUAAGUAACAGAUCAUUUAGGAAAGAUGGAAAAUCAUAUUAAAUCUAAUGCAUUGCUGGUAAAAUGCUUUUAAUUAAAAAAUACUACGAUGGAAAUAUUAAAAGAAGCUAAGUAAUAUAAAAAGUUAGGGGCCAGGUGCGGUGGCUCAUGCCUUAACCCCAGCACUUUGGGAGGCCAAGGUGGGUGGAUUGCUUGAGGUCAGGAGUUCAUGACCAGCCUGACCAGCAUGGUAAAACCCCAUCUCUAUUAAAAAUACAAAAAUUAGCCAGGCUUGGUGGCACAUACCUCUAAUCCCAGCUGCUUGGGAGGCUGAGGCAAGAGAAUCGCUUCAACUCAGGAGGCAGAGGUUGCCUCCUGAGUGCAGAGAUCAUGCCACUGCACUUCAGCCUGGGUAACAGAGCAAGACUCUGUCUCAUAAGAAAAAAAAAAGUUGGGAAAUACUCUCAAGUGUAUCUGAAGAUAAGAAUGAAAAACAACCAUGCAAAACUUAGAUUUAUAGUUUAAAUCCAUGGAAAGAUCUCUAAGAUAAGCUAGGUUGAAAAGCACAUCACAAAAUAAUAUGCACACUAUGAUUUCAUUUAUGUAAAAAAUGGACAGAAUAAUAAGUAUGCAAUGUUUAUGAAUGUAUAUGUUUACAUCCAUACAAUACAUUUUUAUACUAUUUAUACCAUAAAGACAUAAAGUAUAUGCCAUAUAUAUUAGAACCUCAGUACAUUAAGAAAAAAUCUGGAAGAUAGGUAUCAAAUUCCAUGCUUUGUAUACGGAAAGUAUAUAUGUGGGAUGUGGGAAGGUUGACGAAUUCUUUUUAUUUAAUCUUUAGCAUUACUUGGAUUUAUUUGUAGCAAUAAGCUUAUAUUCAUGUAAUGAUUUUUGAUGAGAAAAUAUACUUACGUAUUGAAGUAAAAAAUGACCCAGGAAAAUUGCAGUUCUAGUCUAAAUAGUCACAUGAAUAUAUCCCUAGAAUAUCUUGAAGAGAAUAUAGUAUUGGCUAACAGUCAUCAUAGCUUGAUAGAGAAUAAAGUCUGUCAGACUUAUCUAACAGGGUGAAAAGCCUAGUCAAUUGAGGAAGGAACAAUGGAUAUAAUGUAGUUUUUAAAUAUUUUGCUUCUUACUGAAAAAUGCACUUCUCACUGUCCUGGAAAAAUAUAGACUGGGCUGCUGGUGAUAAAGGAUGGCAGUUAUAAAGUGGUAGACAAUUUCAAUCUGAGAUAAGAUAUAAUAUAUGGGAAUAAGAUGAACUUUAUUAUUUUAAUCAGUGAUCCAAAUUAUUAUAUGUUCACUCAAAAUACAGAUAGUAUAAUCAUGUAAUAUUUUUGUAAUGUUUUCUAUAAUCAGGUACUGGUUUGAAUAGAGGACAAAAAUAAAACAGAAGGUUUGAAGACUAAGUACUUCUUUUUAAGUGACUGAAACAUGUACUUGAAAAACACUUUAAGAACCUUUGUAAAAUAACAUUAAACUGAGUGUGUAAAUAUGCCUUGUAAAAAAAAAAGCAAUUAGAAUUCUGUAGAGUUAAUCACAGUGUGCUUUUGGGGAGGACCUGAGUUAAUCAGGGUUUAGGUGGAGUUUAGAUACUAGUUUGUCACAGAAGAGGGUAAUUCAGGUAAAGACAAAGCUUCCAAUGGGUGAGAGGAUUGGGAAGCUUAUUUUUACUAGUUUGAAAGCUGGGAUUAAAAUUCAGAGUAGCCUGGUAAAUUAGGGAAAUGAUUUGAAAUAAUAUACCGUACCUUUACUUUUAUGGUUCUAAAAUUUUAUUUCCCUGAAUGUAGUUUCGAAAAGAAAGAAGUAGAGAAAGGGGGAAAAAUUAUUUGCACAAAAAAUAAGGAAAUGAAUAGGUCCUUGCAAUUAUGACUAGAGAGUCCAUUGGAGUCUGAAGUGUUUUCUGAAUAUGAGUUGGAAAUGAAAACACUAGUUAAGGCAGCAAACAUGCAAGAAUACUAGCUAAGGUUCUUUUUUCUUUCACAAAUAAAUUUUUUACCCAGGUUGAUCCCUAGGAUCAAUAGUAAAUAGUACACAAUUAAAACUAUAAAUCAUCUAUAAAUGCUGAAAGUAACAAAGGAUGCAGCUUAUGUUUUCUCCAUUUUCUUUAUAAGUUUUGUUUGCAUCUAAUUUAUUUCCAGGUACCCCUAUGAUGUAAAUUACCAUCCAGUCUUCACCUACUACCAGAAAUUGAACUUUUUUAUUUCUUCUGAAAGUUUAAAGAGUUCUAAUAUGGCUCUGUAUUUUUUUUAGCUAAAAUGUCAUAGUGAAUUUCUUUAAACGGUGGUUAUUGUUGACUCAGUGUUUAUCUCUUUUUCACAAAGGGUUUGCCAGUGUCUUUCUUUGACAAACAUGUGUUGUUACUAUUAUGUGCUCACUGGGAUAGUGAGCAAAAAUAGACAUAGGUCUUGAUCUCCCGGAACUUAUAUCUAAAGAUAGAAAAGGAUAUUAAUGAAAUAAUCAUACAAAUAAAUGCAAAGUUGGAACUGUUUCAGUUGCUGUAGAGAGGUACGUAAUAUGAGGGCUUUUAGAAGGAGAAUUUACUCAGUGCGAUCAAGAGGAAUUUUUUUUUGGAGGAAGUGUUUAUUUAGCUGAGAUCUCAAGUAAGUUAAUUUGAUCAAGAUGAAGAAAAGAGUUUUCUGGGAAGAAGGAAUAGCAUAUACAGAGGUUCUGAGGUGGGAGGAAGCAUAGUACCGAAUAUUAAACAAAGGUCAAUGUGGCAGAAGUUUAGAGCAAGAGUUUGCAUGGUAAGUGAUGAUGCUAGGGAGUUAUGUAGGAGCCAAACUGCAGAACUUUGUGUAGGCCAAGCUUUCCUUUAUCCUUAGGUUUAAUAUUUAAACUUAGACUAAUGUUCCUUAGGUUUAACAAGAAAAACCUACUAUUAAUUAUAAAAGAUUUGUGUUAUAGAAGUUCAUUUUUAUUUCAGUUUAAAACCAAUAAUGCUUUUUCCCAUAGAAUCAUGGUUACAGUGACAGGUCUCAUAAGAAACCCUUUUAACAGAAAUAACAUUGGAAACCAGUCAACGUAGUGUCAUAAAUAUAACCAGGUAGAAGUUAGAAAAGAAAAGGAAGGAGAUUAAAAGUUAUGUCUAUAUGUAUUCAAAAGAGAAUGUCCUGGGUAUGAUUGACUAAGCUGUGAAUAAUGAAGAAAAAAGCCUUACUUCAAGUGCAUUAGGCUGGUGCAAGAGAUUCUAACAAAUGAUGGUGAGGGACACAUUCAGCUGGACAGCUUAGAAGAUCCUUAGCUGGCACCUAGAUAUAGAACAGAGUGAUAAUGUCGAGCAAACCAAGGUAGAAGGAGAGUAGAAGUAUCACAUUCAUAAUUUGUUCUGAAUUUAGCACAUAUUCGUGUCAGUUGUUAGAAUAUAAACAUUUAAAAAAUUAUAUACUGGUAAGAAAUGCAGAGCUACCAAAUGUCAGCAAUACAGAUGCCAACUUUAUUUUGAUUAUAUUGAGAGUGAUUUCAUACAGUUAGAAGUGAUUAUAAAUUGCUCAGUUGUACUAUUUUAGGCCAUAAUGUUAGCUUUGAAUAUCUUAGUGUGCAUCACUUGGAGUGAUACUUUAAAGAGGAAGUUGAAGAAAUUUAAUUUUUUAAUUCUUAUUUUUCUUUUAACUUAUUGUCAAUAAAUUAUCUUCAUUUCAGGUUGAUCUUAAGUUUUAAGCCUCUUUGGACACUAGUUUCUGUCUGUAUUAAGUAAUUAACAAUCUAAUAACUGAAAAUUCAAGGAAUGCCCAAAAUAUUAAGAGCAUUAUAAAAAAUAAUUGAUUAAGCAACUUUUAUUAAGAAGAAAAUAUCACAAAGAUGUAAUAAAUUGUAAGAGACAAGGAAGAUAUGUACAAGUCUUCAUUAAAUAAACAGCGUACCACAUAACAGUUGAUGAAUUCUGCCAAUGCUUGAAGUUGAAAAUUGAUGAAGGUACUUCAUCAGGUGAUCUUGAACUUAAUUUUCUCGCAUUCUCAGGUACAGCAGACCAUGCUUUUACAGCAGAUUGGCAUCUAAAAAUAAGAACUAUAGAAUUUAGAGCUUAUUUAUUUGUUUACUUAUUUUUAAAACAUUCCAAUUGAGAAAAUACCAGCAUUGAUUCAUUUUCCAUGCAAUAUCUAGCAGGCUACUUUUAAUUAAUAGACCAACAGUGUUCGGAAAGCUUAUUAGAAUGUUUGACAGCCUGGGCACCAUGGUGAAACCUCAUUUCUGCAAAAAAUGCAAAAAUUAGCCAGGCAUGGGGGCAAGUGCCUGUAGUCCCAGGUCCUUUGGAGGCUGAGGUAGGAGGAUCACUUAAGCCUGCGAGGUCAAGGCUGCAGGGAGCCGUGAUGAUGCCACUGUACUCCAGCCUGGGUGACACAGUAAGACCCUGUCUCAAAACAAAAGAAUGUUUGAAAAGACAGUUUACUAAAUUUAUCUAAUAAUUCUAAGAGGUCAGUGUACCUCUUAAAUAGAAAUGAAGUUUCACUUGUGCAUUUUUCAGGGAUUGAUACGUUUCUUCUAUUUUACAGCUUUCUACUGUUGUUUAGCGAAGCGUAUUCCAAGGUCCUCUAGUUCUGUGAUAACUUAAUAGGUAUGAUUAUCCUCGCACCUGAAAAAACCCAAAAGGCUGCUUCAUCAAAUAAGGUUUAAAAACCAUGAUUAUGAUUAACGAAUGCUGGAUAAACAUUUUUACUGCAAUAUUUUUUCAAGGGGUCUUAAUAUGUAAUUCUUCUGAACUUCUAAUAAUGGUCACUAACAUUUAUUGAGUACUUUGCGCCACUCAUUGUGCUAAAAGUCUUGUAGACAUUAUCUUAUUUUAUCAUUAUAACAAACAAACAUUCUGAGGAACAUACUUAAUGAAGUGUUUCUUCAUAUUUCACUGCUUAUAAACACCUACCCAAAAAUUUAACGUGAAGAAUACAAAAGUGAGACAAACAUCAUUUUCUUUUGUUGCAUCCUUAGCGGCUUUGAGAAAGAAAGGUCAUGAAAAUUAUUUUUAAAGUUAAGUGCUGAGCUUAUCAAUAUGUUUUUACACUCUUCUAAUUACUAUUACUCACAGAUGACCAAUGAUAAACAUUAUACCCUUUUUAUUAAUAGGCGACAACCUGUAGAGCUUUCAGAGACAUUCCUGGGUUUGAGCAUUGGCUCCAUAGACUGAAUACUACAAUAUAGAACCUUUAACGAGCUGUUAAAGUUCUGAACUUUAGUUUAUCAGUAAAAUUAGUAUGGUAAUGCAUAUCUCAGAGUUGUCAUGACUAUGAAUGAUAGAGUAUGAAGUCCUAGAAUGUUGUGGACAUUCACUAAAUUUUUUCAUUUUCCUUCUCUCCUAUUACUAAUAGCAUCUACUACCAUAGUAGAUGAAAAAAAAUGAAAAAAAUGGAUUGUUACCUUUAUUAAUAACAAAAUAUCACAAAGAUGAAUUAAUUCUAAGAGAGGGAAGAUAUGUGCAAGUCUUCGUUGAAUAAGCAGGGUGCACUAUUAGUAAUAGUAGAAGGCGAGAAGGAAAAUGAAAUUAUAUUACUAUUAAUAACUGUUCUAUAAUCUGUAUGUUAUGCGUUAAAAAUUUUUUCUUUUUUUAGAAAUAAAAUUAUCUGUUAAUCUUAAAGCUAUUUUAAAGCUUUCUUGAACUCCUACAUUUUUCUGAGGACUGAUAUACUUCAUUUUUGUGCUGUUCUGCACUUUGCCAACACAGUAAGACCCACAAAGUGGACAUCUGUAAACAUGAAACUCAGAUGGUGGAGAAAUUUGAAUAAAUGCUCCCCAACUUGGUUAAUGUAAAUAUUCUCAUAACUUACAGCAUUGGUUUUGGUGAUUGUUAUUAAGUGAACAAAUAUGUAAAUAUAUUUUCUUUCCUUGUCUUUGUUUCCUCACAUUAGGUAGGCAAUAUUGCAAAAACGUUAAGAGCACGGACCCUAGAGCCAGACUGUCUGGAUUCAAAUCCCUGCUCCACCACUUAACUAGCUAUGGGAUAUUCUGUGCCUCAGUCUCUUCAUUAGUAAAAUGGGCCUAGUCAGUUGUGUCCACCUCAGGGUUAUUUAGUGAGUUUAGAUAUAAUCAAUGCUUUAGAUAUAUACAAUGCUUUAAAAAUGCCUGGUUCAUGCUAAGUGACACAAAAGUAUUAACUGUUAUAGUGAUUAUAUGUGUUGUCUUUAUAUUAGUUGUACUAUAGAAAAUAGUGACUAGUAUAUUAUGGUAAAUCUUUAACUUGGUAAUAUUUCAUUUGGUACAAUAAAACAAAUUCUAUUUAUAGUUCUUUGAAAUGUAUACCAGACUUUUCAAAUGACACUUUUAUGUGUCUUUUUACAUUUGCCAGAUUCUUUACAUUAUUGUUUUACUUCUUGUUGAGGGAGAUAGUGGGAAAAAUAUCUUUGUUGUUUCUCAUAAAGAAACAGACAUACAGAGUGUUUAGGACCUUUUAAAGUAUAGCAAUAAGAAAGUCAGUGGAAAGACUAAAAUUAGAACCCAACAUAUUCCAUGUGCCAAUGUGUUGAGCCAAGCUAUCUGUUCUCCUUAUUGAGAAUUCAAACAACAAAACUAUUAGUUGACAUUCUCCUCAUUGAGAAUUCAAACAACAAAACCAUUAGUUGGCAAAGUAAAUGUAAAGAUAUGUUCUUCUGUUGUUUAAAAUUGUAUUAGCUUGUGUCUGCUUUGGAUAUAUCCUCUUACUUAAGGUUGGUUCACUCAAAGAUUACUUGAAAAGUUUGAUUUAAAUGGGUGUAGACAAUUAAAGUUAAGUAUUGGGCUAGCCAUCCCUUAGGACAUUUAAGGGCUGAAUAUCUUUUUUAGCCAUCAACUGGCUUUUUCUCCAUCUUUGAUGAACUAGGUCAAAAACUCCUAUUUCUCAUAGUCAGUACUCUAGUACUAUAUAUGGGCUCAGUGCUCCUGUGAGCCAUCCUAGAAACUUAACUGUCAUUCUUAGUAUUUCAUUUCUAUUAAGUGAUUCCAAGUUUCAGGGAAUAAAUUAGUGAGCAAUGAGGUUUUGAACAGCACUAGAUUUAUAAGGUGAACAGUAUCUAUGUUUUAAUUUUCAUAUUAAAGAACAUUUUAAAUAGGUUUUUAUUUUUUCUUAUUUAAACUAUUACAGAGUGUGUAACUCAUAAGUUUAAGAAACUGAUGAACAGUUUGGUUGGGGGACCCAGAAAAUAAUAAAUAUUGGCAAUCAAAACACUCAGAAGCAUUUUUAAAGAGAUAAUUAUAAAUGGUUGCGUAGAUAACAAAAGUAAUUUCAAAUUUAUAAUUUAUGCUCAUAAUUGCUUAAGACGUAGGGUUUUUAUGUAAAGGCAGAAUGAAUUUUCUCUUCCAAAAUAACCAAACUUAACAUUUAGUAUACUACUCUAAAAAUUGCAAACACUUAAUGGAGAUUUUUACAUAAAGGCCACUUUUAUUGUAGAAAACUAAACAAAGAUAAUUUGUUUGUUUCAAAUAACCAAGUAUUGACUGGAUUCUGGUACACAACAUCCCUGGUAUUUUUCAUAUGAAAUAAUGCUUAAAUGUUAUAAACAAGUUCUACAAAAUGUUCUAAAAUCUUUUUUGGUAUUUUCAUAUAUUCAUUCUGCAUAGAAUCAGGAAACCUAAUCACCCAGUAACCCAGUUUGAAAACUCAUAUUAUUUUGUAAAUCCUGAUGUAAUUAAACCACUUUAAAUGUCUGCUAAAAAAUAUCAAGUUAUAUUUACAUAUGCUUUUUUAAAGUUAUGCCUUGUGAAAAAUAUUAUUAUCUUUAAAUGAGACAGUUAGAGACAUCUUAAACUAUUAAGGUUAACAUCAGCUGCUAAGAGACAUCAAAUCCUGAUUCAAGAGAAUAGUAAUAUUUUCAUAAGCAGAAAUUUUUCUCAAAGAGAAAAAACAGAAUGUGCAGUGUAUUCGCAUUAUAAAUGCAGUUAGGAAAAAUGCAUUUACAGAAAGUCCCAGGACUUGAGAAGCAAGCUCAGGUUUUUCAUAGUGAUGUAGAGAAGCAUAAAUGUUCAUUAAUUCAGUUACUCAUUCUAAAAAUAUUAAGUACUUACUGUAUGCCAGUUAUUCACCUAUGAAUAAGACAGGCAAGGACUAUGGAGCUUAUAGUCUUUCCACUGAAGACCAAUACUAAGGAAAUAUUUAUGAGUGAUAUACAUUACAAAAGAACAAACAGUUCUUUUCAGCUAUUUAGAGAAUGCAGAUACAAGUUGAGUUGUAAAGCAAACAUUUCUAGGUGAUAAUAAUAAAAGCAUUAAUUUUUCAUUCUCUCAAUGUUUUGGAUCAGGAGAAAGAGACCCAGAAAAGGUCUCUUAUCCAAGGUUAUAUAACAACUGGUAUAUCUGGUACCUCGGUCCCCUGCCUCCUAGUGUAAUAAUAUCUGCCAUAAGAAAUAAAGCAGGAAUGUGAAAGAGAAGAAAGUCAGGCAGGAUGCCUAGAAAGUUCAACCAGACACUGGAUUUCAGUGUAGUCUAUAUAACAGGAGGAAUCACAUUUUUAAAACUUCUUUUAUGCUUGUUUUAUACAUUUCUUUUCAGUUUCUUUUAGCAUUUACUAAAUCUUUCAGGACUUUGCUAAGUUCCAUACAUCUACAAAAUUUCUAAACAGGAGUCUUAUGUCCCUGGAAGCAAACUAUGUUGGUACUAUGGUUCCUAAAUCUCAUCUCUACAAAAACUUUUCAGGGUUGUAUCUUUUUUCUUUUUUCUCGGUAAAGAAGGUUGUUUUCUUUAAUUACCUUGAAUUUAAUAAGUACAGUCUUAUGAUUGCUGACAAAAAAAAAAAAAAGGAAAAGAAAAAGAAAACUUGAGGAUUGGGGAAAUUAAGGACACAUUUUUUUUUCCUGGGAUGGUUUUGAUGUAACACCAGUUUGUAAUCUUCUUACUGUGAAUUAAUCUUCACUGUAUCUGAUAAUAAAAGAGUUUAUAAUAAGUUAGAAAGCAUAUCCCAUCAAUCACAUGUAAGGUUUUGACUAAACUAACGGAUAAAGAUUUGUAAGGAAGUUAGGUGAUUUUAUCUUACUGUCCAUUGUAUUUUUUUAAUUUGGUUUUUGAUGUUACUGUUUAAAUUAUACCAGGUUAACGAAGGGUUUGAUUUUUGUUUCAAAAAUAUAUAUUAAAUAGAAAAACUGAGUACACAUCCUAAUACUUACUUUGACUUGGGGACAGCAAAGCACAAUUAUAGGAUCACACUUUGAGAAGUAAAUAAACUGUUUGAAAAUUGAGUCUGCAAAGCUAGACAUAGUAACAACAGGAAACAUCCCACCUACAAUGCAUAUGGCAAAGGAGAAAGAUAGUGCAGCAGACUACAGACAAAAAUAAUAGCUGAGAGCUGAAAACAAGUAUUCUGCUUUACAACCUUAGAUCUGUCAUCUCAAAAAUAGAGAUAAUCUUUCUUCAAAAUAUAAUAUGGUGAUGUGAGCAUAUUUUAAUUUAUAAGAAAAAUCUUUUUCUUUAGGUAUCCCAUAUCAUAUUUUUGCAUUCUUUAUAGUGGAGGGUACAGUGUCUCCUGUAUGUUUUAAACCUUAUUAUUUUUCUGGUGUAUAUUUGUUGUUUUGUCUUCUAGGGACACAUACUAUUUUUACUUUACUAAUGUGCCAAAUUUUAAGAAAUUUAAUACUUAAAAAACCGAAUAUGCAAAGUUCGUAAAGUAAAUGGUGAGAAGAUUUCACUGAAGAAUUGCUUUAAAUAGAAAGCUCUUCUGAUGUACUUAAGUGUUUGUAAAGUCACUUCCUACCCUGGGCUAAAAGAGACACAAGAAAACUCGAGGCUUAAAAUGUUGGAAAUCACUGUUGCUUGAAUAGUAAGCAGAAAUGAGGGUAAAUCAUUUCUGAAAUUUUAAGUAUAAACUAAUGAAAAAUUGCUUUGCUAUAGAAAUUGCAUUUUCAUCUAAUUGAAUAUAUUCAUUUUAUUAAGUGGGUUACUACUGUGUAUUCUUUAAUUUCAUUAUCUUCAAGAUUAAUUUAUAGAGUCUAUAUGAAAAUACUACGUGGAAUAGGAGUUAUAUUUUAUAAGGAGUUGCUGUGUUUUAAGGAGUUAUGUUAAAAUCACAUUAUCUGGUGAGUAUCAGUUAACCACAAGGGUACUGGCCAGUCAGUUAUGUUUCAAAAUACCUGUUACUUAGUUUGAGAAAAAGUGACUUUGGGCACAUAUUCCUGCUUCUUAUUUUGUAAAAGGGAAUGCUGUGGUUUGUAAUACUAGGCUAUUGUCUAGUUUGAUUCAAAGCACCCUACUCCAUUCAGCCUGGGCAAGAUAGUGAGACCCCAUCUCUACAAAAAAUUUAAAAAUUAAGGGCGGGAGGAGGGAGAGGAUCAAAAAACUAUGUAUUGGGUACUAUGCUUAUUUCUUGGGGGACAAAAUAAUCUGUGCACCAAACUCCUGUGACAUGCAGUUUACCUAUCUGACAAACCUGCACAUGUACCCCUGAACCUAAAAUAAAAGUUAAAAAGUAAUAACUAAAUAAAUAACAAAUAAGCUAGACAUGGUGGCACGAGCCUGUAGUCCCAGAAGGAAGAGGUGGGAAGACCCCUUGGGCCAAGAGGUCAAGACUGCAGUGAGCCAUGAUUGUGUGACUGCACUCCAGCCUUUCAUAAAAAAAUCCCUGCAAAAGUACCCUACUGGUAGAUAAUAUCUUCUUUAAAAUUAUAAAUAAUGUCAUGUUCAUUAAAUCUGAGUGUGUAUACUAUAUGGACAGAAUAGAUUAUCCAGCCUUUUGAUUCUUUAAUUCUAUCUCUCUGUGAUCUAAUUAAAUAAAACUAAGUUACUUUGAUGUAUAUAUGGGUAUUUAUAUCAUUAAUUCAUAAUAAGGCAAAAUAAAUAAUUGCUGUAAGUGACAAUGAUAGCUUUUUAAAAAAUAUAGCCAACAUUAUUUCUGUUAUAUUUAUUCAAACUCCCAAUUUUGAUAACAAACACAAUUUAAUCUUUAUCAUAUAUGUGUAUCCAUUAAUUUAUUUUUGGCCCCAUCCUUAACAGUUAAACAUAUUAUGGCAGUAGUUUUUGUUUUUGCGUGCGUUUUUCUCCUAGGUCUGGAAUAACUAUUCUUGGCCCUGUGGGUGCACAUUAAAAUCAUGUAGGACCAGGCCCUAAAUUUUAAAUCAAAAUCUUUGAGGGUGGAGGCCCUGGUAUUUUUUAAAGCCCCUCACGUGAUGGCUUUACAAAAUAAGCCACAAAAGCACUGGUAGAUGUUAUCUACCAGUGAUAUGCUUUUGUGGAGUUUUGUUUGUUUGUUUGUUUUUGAGUCAAGAUCUAGCUCUGUCACCCAGGCUGGAGUGCAGCAGAUCGAUCAUGGGUCACUAUAGCCUCAACCUCCGGGCUUAAGUGAUCCUCUAACCUCAGCCUCCUGGGACUAAAGGCUCAUGCCACCAUGCCCAGCUUAUUUAUUGAAGUCCAGCCAGUAUCGAGAAUUACUGUGCUAGGGCUAUGAUCCCCUGUGUUAACAUUUUCUUACCUUGCUCUUGAAGGAUCGUUAAACACCAGUUCAGCGGGAGUUGGAGGGCUGACGACACUACAGAAUCUGGACUCUAUGACUUGUUUUGGGAGUAACAGGAGGGUGUGAUGAGGAAUUUCUGUGAAGGUGACUUCUGGAUCCUCAGCUUCAAUUACUGAAACUAUGGAGAGACAUGAAAGCACCCCACCCUGGCUCAGGUCAGGAAAGAAUUAGGAAAGGGGACUUCUGACUGGUUAGGUGAAAUUGAGGAAGGGUUAGAAGUUCAGGAAAGUAAUACUUAAAAGUAGCAGAUUGUAUAGACACUCUUGUUCUGAAGUACCUUGAAAUGGAUUUGGAGAAGAACCACCAUCAGGCCAUCAUGGAUGAUCUUUCUCAGGAGAAAGAUGAGAACCAGUUUACAACAGGCCAUCUAGUUUAACAGCUUUCACUCUUGUACCUGUACACACGUUACACACUUAUGCAUACUCAUGUACAUCAUACACACAAACACUCGUUAUUCUAAAGCAAGUAAGAUGAUGCAGAGAUUGAUUACUGGGGCAAAAGAAGGUUCUGCCUUGGUCUUCACUGCCUUUCUUCUGCUUUCCACCCAUCUUUCCUCUCUCCAAAAACGUAAAAAUCCUUUAAUACCUACUUGCUUGUACUUGAAAUUUUUUAAGGGGAACAAACUUUCUUCUUAAACAAAUAAGAAAGUCUUAACAUGGAAAUAUACACAGAAAUCUUCUCAGAGCAUUGUAUGGUCUUUUAACAAGUUAAAGCCAUCUUUAUCCUUUCCUAUAUUUUAAUCUGAGAGAGAGUGAUAAGGAGAGAAAAGCUCUGGCCACCUAAAGGGGACUGUCUUCUACUUCGUUGUUUACUAUUUACUUUUAAUUGUGAAGAAAACCUAAAAAUAUAUGUGCAAAAGUACUUAUAACCUACCAAACCUCUGCUGAGCACUUUAGUUGCAGAUACCUCAUUAGCAUAUAAUACUCUUGCUUUCAAGAGAUGUGGAAUUUCUCUUUUAUAAGAAUCUAUGUGGAUAUAAAUAGUGGUGAUCAAGGCACUCUUACACUAAGAGUUCAGUGAUGAUACAUCUCUGUCCUUUCUUGGCAAUUUUUGCUACCACUUAUUUUUAGUGCCUAUAUAACAUUUUAAAGUUGCAUCCUCCUUUUUAUGACUGAUGAGAAGCAUAUGCCUCUAUGAGGAAGAAAAGGUAUUUAUGACUUACAGAAAAAAAUUUCUCACAGCUAUGAGUAAGCUAUAGGGAACUGAAAACAAGAGGCCAAAGAACCUUUUUUUUUUUAAUGGCCUUGGUUACAUAAAGAUAUUUAGACCAGCUUUCAAAAAUAACAACAGUUUUUAAAAUUUACCAUAUCGAGCCUCAGUACGUUACUCUAAAACACAGCUUUAUAAUUCCUCUAUAAUCUACAUUAAAUGAAGAGUAAAAUAAAACUACAAAUUUAGGAAGAUGAGGAGGACCAAAAAAACUACAAAUAAGGUAAAUAAGAAAAAUUGCAAACCUCAAAUCUCUUACAAAGAAAAUUAUGAUAUUAAUAGUUUCCUUACUCACAUUUGGUAAUUGUAUAAAGACUGCAGAGUUACUACCUGUACAUCUGAAAAAGGAGAAAAAGGACCUAACCAGUGUUGCUGAAAGAAAUUUUACAAAUAAAGGGAUCGAUCUGGUAGCUAGUCAGGUUUAUUUUUACCUGGGAUUUAGGGCUUCCUGAGGCAAUGUAGCCUUUACCCUUUUUUAGGUCUUAGCUCCCUUUGAAAAUCUGAUGAAAUCAUUAGAUUUGGGGGGUAGGAUGUCUUGUAUAAAAAAUUUUGUAUGGGCUUGUUUAUGUAUUUCAGGGAGUUUGUGAGUGCUCUGAAAACGAAUGAACUCCUAGACCACCUGUAUCGGAAUCACCUGAGUUGCAUAUUAAAAUUGCAGACUAUUGGACUCCACCCUAAUCUUAUUGUAUUAGAAUUUCUAGGCCUGGCACUGUGGCUCACACCUGUAAUCCCAGCACUUUGGGAGGCCAAGGCAGGUGGAUCACGAGGUCAGGAGAUUGAGACCAUCCUGGCUAACACAGUGAAACCCUCUCUCUACUAAAAAUACAAAAAAAAAAUAAAAAAAUAAAUAAAUAAAUAAAUUAGCCGGGCAUGGUAACGGGCACCUGUAAUCCCAGCUACUCCUGAGGCUGAGGCAGGAGAAUCGCCUGAACCCAGGAGGCGGAGGUUGCAGUGAGCCAAGAUCGUGCCACUGCACUCCUGUCUGGGCGACAGAGCGAGACUCCUUCUCAAAUAAAUAAAUAAAUAAAUAAAUAAAUAAAUAAAAGAAUAGACUUUCUAGUUACUUGGGCUCAGGAAUCUCGAUUUUAACAAGGAUUGCCUGAUGGUUCUCUUUCCAUCACUAAAGUUUGAGAAUCACUGCUCUAGAGCUUUAUGGAUUACACCAGUUCUGCCUUUGGCCUAGAAGCAGGUUUUCUUAUUCCCUGUUCAGUGAUACUUGACUCACCAUAUGUUGCCUACCAAUUUCUUACCCAUCUACAAAAUCAGGAUUGUAAAGAAAGAUAUUUGUGCUGGGUUGAUAAUUUUAGUUGAAGGAAAUAAGUCAUUAGAAAUACAUAUUUUAGAUCCUGGGUCUGUCAGUACCUAUGAUUUGCAAAAUAAGUAAAUUUAACUUAUUUCCAGUCUUUUGUAAAACAUAUUUAUUUGCUCUAAAAAUGUAUCUGCAGUUAUUUAAGUGUUUAAUACAUCAGACUGGGAUUUUCAAUUAUAGCUACUUGAAAAUACUGCUAACUCAGAAUAAUUGAGGUCGGAUCCAGUGUAAAUUUUGGGGAAGCAUGACUUACAGAAUUAAAUUAAAAAUAUAUGCAGUUUAACUUCAGAUGUACGUAGUGAUAUGAACUGUCUCCAAGAAGAGUCAUCUUUAUAUCUGAAUAAAGCUUAUUUGUAAUGCAUAUAUUAAGUGGUGUUAUGUAAAUCAAUGCUUUUAAGAUAAUUUAAAAACUGCUUGAAAAUAAUAUGCAAAAUUUGACCAAACAUUUCCUUGCAAAUCUUGUUAUAGUCUUAAUUUAUUUUUGCUGGUUUACUUCACAGAUAAAUUUAGAAUUGAACUUUAGUCUAGUAGGGACAUGCCAUUAUCUCAUUUCCAAUUAUUGGAUCUGGAUUAAUGAGUGAGUAUGCCCAUGGGGCUGAACUAUUUAGUAUUAAGCAGAAACAUUUUUAUACCAUGACACUGAGAACCAGGUUACAAGUCUAGUAUUCCUGUGACUUUUUUAAACACAGAAGAAAAAGUUUCCUAGACAAGGAUUAUGCGAUGUAUUUUAGUCAACUUUCUCAUCAAAUGUGUUGUUGGGAGUCACGGGAGACCAGGUAAAAUAAUGUAGAUGACUCAGUGAAGGAUACUUGUUGCUAAGAGGAAAUAAAUAAAUAUAAGAUGAUGAGUGGGUAAGUCAGAAAUACCUUUUCUGUGUGGGAAAAAUAUAUGCUAUUGUUAUUACUAUUCAUUUGUAUAAUAAAAGUGCCUGUUAAUGUUUAUCUGUGUCUUUCUUAAAAGCAAAUUAAAAUUAGUUCAGUAAAUAUUAUGUAAAAUCUGUUAUUCCUAAAGUCCUUAUUUCUGAGAAACUACAUGAAAAUACCUUAUAAAAAUUUUUCAUGUCUCCUAUGGUCAUCCAAAUUUAUGUAAAGAUAAUAGUUUUGGUAAUUACUCUACAAAGAUUAAAAUUUAGUUGGUGAUUUCCCUGCUGCCUCUUAUUUUCCUCAGUAAAAAUUUAUGUUUUACUAUAAGAUGAUACUGAUUUUUAUGGUAUAUUGUUUGGUAACUGUUGAAUUCAAUUUCUUGGUUCCCUUUGACUUUGUCCUCAUGUAUUCCUCAGUGGCGCACACGUGCACACAUGCACACAAAUACAUCAUUAUGUCUCUGUAAUAAGAGGUGUAUUAUAUUUUCCUAUUUGACAAAAUGGAGUAUAAUGGUUAUAAUAGCAGCUUACUUUUGAUAAGCGUACUAACUGGUACAUAGUAAAUACAUACUGUGCAUGCAUUAUGUCAUUUAUAUCCACACAGUCACCUUCAAAUUCAGUACAAUUUGUAUUCCCGUUUUACAGAUGAGAAAGCAUAUUUUGGUGAACUCAACCAAGGUUACAUGACUAGUAAAUUUUAAAUGAGAUUUAAUUUCAGUACUUACUAACCAUUAUGCAUUGCUAAAUUUGAACAUUACUUUAAAAUAUAACUUCUAAAGUGUUCAUAUUAGAAACCUAUAAAUAUACAUAGAUUUGUCUCCUCUCUUACGAAGAACACAUGAAGGAAAGAAAGAUAUUAAUUUGGUGGCUUAUCAUAUGCCAGACAUAGAUAUAGAUGCUUGUAUGUAUGGCAUUUAAUCCUUAUCUGUGAGGUAGGUCUUUUUAUGCCUUUCUAUAGAUUUAAAUUAAAGGUUCAGUUUAGUAACUUGCUCGAGGUUAUACAGAAUGUGGCAGAACUAAUAUCUGACCCCAUAGUGCUUAUAACUGGUAAAUAAACAACUUGGAUUAGGUCACUUUCUCAAGUGUACUGGAGACUAAUUGCUCCAAGAUAAAAGGCAGAUAGACUGUUACCUACUAGUAAAUGUAAAGAGGAAAUGUCAUUUCUCUUCUUUCUCCAUUGUCUUUAUGCUAUUAAGUAUGUUAGAAUUUGUAUAUAGCAAUCUAGAAAUUUUGAAAACUUCCCCUCUUAAUCCUAGAAUGGAUAAUAAAAUUGUUUCCUAAUUUAUGUACACAAUCAUGGUUCACACUAGUCAAACAGUUCACCAAGGGCUUGUUGUUAGUAUUGUCUUAAUGAAGUGCCUUUUUUUUUUUUUUUUUUUUUUUUUUUUGAGACAGAGUCUCGCGGUGUUGCCAGGCUGGAGUGCAGUGGUGCAAUCUCGGCUCACCACAACCUCCGCCUCCCAGGUUCAAGUGAUCCUCCUGCCUCAGCCCCUCGAGUAGCUGGGACUACAGGCGUGUGCCAUCACACCCAGCUAAUUUUUGUAUUUUUAGUAGAGACGGGGUUUCACCAUGUUGGCCAGGACGGUUUUGAUCUCUUGACCUUGUGAUCCGCCCACCUUGGCCUCCCAAAGUGCUGGGAUUACAGGCAUGAGCCACUGCACCCAACCUUAAUGAAGGCUUUUUAUACACUAGUGAUGUUAUGAAAGAAAUAAAAUACAAGGUUUUCGAAGUUUUGUGAUUGGUUGAGAAAUCUACUUAAACACAUCAAAAUAAUUCAGCAUAUGAUUAAGUUGUAGACUGAGUGGUUAGCAGUAUAAGUCCCUGAGGUCUUUCAAACUGAGUAUUUAUGUAAUUACUCAUUAACAUCUCCCACAAACCUCUUUUGCUUGUAUUUACUUUCUUGGAUGGUGCUGUCCCUGUCUACCCCAAUUCCCCAAGUUAGAAAUAUCAUAGUCCUCUUCCACCCCUUCUUUACCUCCAUAGUCAGCCUAUCACCAAAUCGUAUAGAAUUGUUUUCCUUCCUAAUUCCUAAGUCCGCUCAGUUCUAUCUUUGUGUUAUGCACAUUGCUGCUAGUUUAGUUCAUUCCUUGACUAGAGAAUGGUAGUAAGUAAUCUCCUUAGCUAAUUAAUCUGCCUCUGACUUUUCUGUACUCUGGGCCAUAUUCUGUCUUUUGCUGAGUUGUUACCAAACAUAAACCUGGUUAUGUCACUACCCUAAUUAAAAACCUUGUGGAUUGUUCCUUUUUAUUGGUUUAUAUAAAAUCCUAUUUUCAAUCUGAAGUAUAAGCCCUUCAUCUUUAUAUCUUAUGUCAACUUAGACCUCCAGCUUCAUCUCCCAUUACUUUUCCCCUUAUGAUGUCUUUCAUCGCAGCUAACCAACCCACUUCCUCUUCAAGAUUAUGUUGUGCUCCUUCAGGUCUCCUUGGCUUUAUUCACAUGCUGUCUUUUGUACAGUGCCUCUUGCCUUAUCCACUGUCUCCCCCAACAUAGUUUUACUGCAAAUCCCAAAUCAGGUGUCACUUCUUAUCAAAUCAUCCUGGCCAUCCUCAAUUUUCCCCUUCUUAGUUAAUGAUGCACUCAUUUAACUUUUAUGAUCAUAUAAGAUGGUUGUUUUUUUACUUCUAGUGUCAGUCACCAAGAUUAUCAAGUUCUUGCUUUGUUUUCUUUUGCAUCUUCAAAUCUAGCUCAAGCCAUAACUAAGACCAUGACCUUUACUAAGGGUCAUACAAACCUGAAUUGAAGUAAGGGCUCUGCAACCAAAAGAAAUGGAGUACAUUUUGCGUGGAGACAGAGGAAGUUUUAAAAAGGAUCAUGGGCAAUGGCAAUUCUAGAUGUUUUUUACAUCCUGCUUGGCCAGAAUUAAGCAGAUAAUACCUGAAUAUACGAGAAGGCCAAAUUGGGAGAUGUAGAAAUUGUUAACCAAUAUUUUUACCAAGUGCCUUGAUAAAUGUUUGUGUUUGUGCCACACAGGCACUAGGGGUACAAAGAUGAAUAAGAAAGGAACUCUGCCUUUGAAGAAAUUUAGAGUGACUAGGGGAGAAAGACAUGUAAAUAAAUGUAUAAGGUCAUCUAGAGUAUUCAUUUAAUGAAGUAAUUGUAAAGAACAGCAAGCAACCACUUAGGAUGAGAAUACCUCCUUUGGCAGAAUGGCCCUAAGUCCAAAGUGAUACCUUAGCUAAAUUUUAAGUUAUGAGUUGGAAUUCUACAAUUGCAUAAGAUGGUAAGGGCUUCCUAGACUAAGAGAACAGCAUGUGCAAAGACACGAGUUACAAAAGCAGCAAAACUAGAGAAACCAUUGUUUGUGAGAUCUCAUACAUAGAGUUGUUUAUUUUAGAAAGCCUCACAAAGAAGCCUCUAGUAAGAUACUGUAGAUAAUUCCCAACUUAAAUAUGCUGUCUUGAAACAAUCCUCUUAUAUCAAUUUAUUCAUUGUUCUUUCCCUUUGAAGUCUAAGGUGGAUAGGGGCAUAAACUUUGGUGAUGAUUAAUUUAAGUUCAGAUCCUGAAACAUUCUGUCUCUGUAAAGCAUCAUUUUACCUGUUCAAAAAAAGGUUACUAACUACCUCCUUCUCAUGGUUUUUGGAAGAUUCAGAGGGAUAAUGCAUACAAAGUUGUUGACACAAUGCCUGGUCCGUCUCAGUAGGACUCGAGAAAUGUUAACAUAUAUUAAGGCUCCUGAUAGGCCUUUUUUGGUUUCCCACCCAUUUAUUUAAGAAAUUGUUUUUUAAAUGCUUACUACUUAUUAGGUGCUGGAAUUAUGAAGAUGAGUAAACACAACAUCUGCCUUUGAAGAAUUUAUAGUUUAGUGAGGAUAUGCACAUACCUAUGUUGAAAAUCAACAAUAAUAAUACAACCUGGCAAAUGCUUUAGUGGAGAGUUUUGUGAGAAAAUAAGAACUGAGAAAAGAAGCCGCCAAAUCUAUUUUUGGACAUUAGCAAAGUCUUCUUCAGGGAGCACUGACCUGAAGAAUGAAGAGCAGUUUGCUGUUUUGGAGUUGGAGAGUAGAGAAGAGUAAGGCUUUCCAGGAAUGAGGAAGAACAUAUUCAAAAGGAGGGUCAAGGUAACAUGACUUGUUCAGUAAAAGACAAAUGAUAAGAAAACCACUAAAAGAGAAAAGAAUGGAGUAGAAAACAGAGGACUGAAUGUACUCAGGGGAAACUCUGUGGUUGAAAAGUCCCCCAGAAGGCCUAAAGUUACUACUUUGCUCCCUUGAGAAAAGAAGUGAAUAAAUUUCCUAGGGUGGGUAUGAGAUAAGCCUCUCUGUGAAAAAUUGCCCUGUCUCAUCCUGGGAUGUUGGAAUAGUCUAGUCCACUCUUCUUACAUGAAUUCUUGUGUACUCCCAGAAAGUACUGCAGUGCUCAAAGGGUGAGGCAGGAGGAGCAAAGAAAUAGAAUUUCAUUAGUGAUGUUAGUGUCUGAGAAGUGGUGCCAGCAAGAGUCAUAUUGACCACAUUGUGGGAAAUGGUAAAAAAGAAGCAUUUUCCUGUGGUUGCUGGGAGUUUCUGGUAACAUGUGAUGGAUUGACUGGACUGUAGCUUGACUAGACAGUGGCAUCAACCUGUGUAUUCACUGGUUCUCAGCUGCCCAGUGAUUGUACCCAGAAACUGGACAUCACCUUAGCUCUUUAGAAGCUAGAAAUCUUGUGGCAAGUGGAUUUCGUGCACCAUCCAUUCUUCACUUUGCUUUGAACCAAGGGAGGAAUUUGGAUAGCACUAGAAAUUUAUGGAAAUCUGUCAGUGGGAGCUAGCCAUAGAAUAAUUGUUAUGCUGUGGUUUUGCACUCCAGCUGUAUUUCUAGCUAGUUAGGACUAUGGCAAUAUCUUUUGAACAAGAAAGCAAACAGGAAAAAUAACUGAAAUUUGUUGAGUAAUUACUGUUUACCUAGUACUGUAGUACUUGCUUUCUGUGGGGGAGAAGGGUGGCUUUCAUUUUUUAUUGAGGUAAAAUCCACAUAGCAUGAAAUUUACAAUUUAAAUCAUUUUAGAGCAUGCAAUUCCUUGGUUUUCAGCAUAUUCACAUUUUUGUGGAGCCAUCACCAAAUCUAAUUCCAGAAUAUUUCUAUCUCCCUGAAAAGAAACCCUAUACCUGUUAGCAGUAACUUCCAAGUACCUCCCUCCUUCCCAUAUCGUCUGGCAACUUCUAGUCUACUUUCUAACUAUAUAGAUUUGCUUAUUCUGGACAUUUCAUAUAAAUGAAUUUAUAUAAUAUGUGGCCUUUUGUGUCUGGCUUCUUUCACUUGAAUAAGGUUUCAUUCAUAUGCUAAUGUGCAUCAGUACUUCAAUCUCCUUUAUGGCUAAGUAAUUUUUCAUAUGAGGAUGUACCACAUUUUGUUUAUCCAUUCAUCAGUAUUUGGUGAUGGACAUCUGGGUUGCUUUCACUUUUUGGUUAUGGAUAAUGCUGCUGUAAACAUUUGUGUACAAGUUUUUGUGUUAACAUAUAUUUUAACACAUUCCUAGGAAUGUAAUUGCUGGGUCUCAUGGUGACUCUAUGUUUAACAUCCAAGGAACUACCAAACUGUUUUUCAAAGUAGCUGCACCAUUUUCAUUAGCAUACGAGGGUUCCAGUUUCUCAGCUUCCUUACCAACACUUGUUGUGUCUUUUUUGUUACAGCCAUCAAGUGAGGUUGAAAUUUUAUCUCAUUUGGUUUUGAUUUGCCUUUACUGAUGGCUAACGAUGUUCCAAAUGUUUUCAUGUGCUUAUUAGCCAUUUGCAUACCUUCUUUAGAGAAAUGUUUAUUCAAAUCCUUUUCCAUUUUAGAGAAAUGAUUAUUCAAAUCCUUUUCCACUUUUUCGUGUUUGCCUUUUCAUUAUCUUUUUAUUAUUGAAUUGUAAGAGUUCUUUAUACAUUUUGGAUACUAGACCCUUAUCAUAUAUGAUUGCAAUAUUUUCUCCCAUUCUGUGUGCUGUCUUUUCACUCUCUAUAAUGUCAUUUGAUCCACAAAAAUUUUGUCUCAAUAAUUUUUUUCUUUUGUUACUUUAACUUUUGGUGUUAAUUUAAUAGAUUAUUGCCUAUUCCAAGGUUAUGAAAAUUUACAUUAUAUCUUGAAGAGACUAUAUCCCCCCAUUGAAUUGCCCUAGCACUCCUGUCAAAAAUCUGUUAAUCAAAGACAUGUGGGUGUAUUUCAGGCUUUCAGUAAUAUCCUGUUGGUCUGUACGUCUCUCCUUAUAUCAAUACUACACUGUUUUGAUUACUGUAGCUUUGUGUAGUAAGUUUUGAAAUCAAGAAGUGUGUUUCCUUACUAUAGUUUUUUUGUUUCUUGAUUUUUCUAAGAUUGUUUUAGCUAUUCAGGGUUCCUUAUAUUUUCAUAUGAAUUUUAAAAUCAGCUUGUCCCUUUCUGAAAAUGAAAAAUAGACUGUUGAAAUUUUAGUAGGAGAUUGUAUUGAGUCUGUGGAUCAGUUUGGGAAUUAUUGCCAUCUUAACAGUAGUAACUCUUCCAGUCCAUGAACAGUAUGUCUUUUCAUUUCUGUACAUUUCCUUUAAUUUUUUAAACAGUGUUUUGUAGUUUUCAGUGGACAAGUCUUACACUUCUUGGCUAAAUUUAUUCUUAAGUAUUUUAUUCCAUUUAAUGCUAUUGUAAACAGAAUUGUUUUCUUAAUUUCAUUUUUGGUUUGUUCAUUGCUAGUUUUUAGAAAUACAACUGCUUUUUGCAUAUUAAUUUUGUAUUCUGCAUUUUUGCAGACCUUAUUAGCUCUAAAAUAUUUUAGUGGAUUCUUCCGGGUUUUUUAUACAUAAGAUUAUGUCAUCUGCAAAUAGAAAUAGUUUUACUUCUAAUCUGGAUGUCUUUUCAUUUCUGUUUUUCUUUUUUUUUUUUCGCCCAGUUUCCCUGGCUGGAAUGCUUAGUACAAUAUUGAAUAGAAGAGGUGUGAGCAGACAUCCUUUUCUUGUUCCUGAUUACUUAGGGGAAAGCUUUUACUGUCUUACCAUUAUGUUAGUUUUGAGGUUUUCACAGAUGUUCUGUCAGGCUGAGGAAAUUUCCUUCUGUUCUGUUUGUUGAGUGUGUGUGUGUGUGUGUGUGUGUGUGUGUGUGUGUGUGUGUGUUGUCAUGAAAGGAUGUUAUAUUUUGUCAUAUGCUUUUUCUGCAUUUGUUGAGAUGAUCAUAUGGUUUAAUAUAAUCACAAUUAUGAUAUAAUAAUUCUUCUAGAUUAAAUUUUAUAGUAUUUUGUUGAGUAUUCUUGAAUUUAUAUUUAUAAGAGCUAUUGAUCUAUAGUUUUCUUGGGAUUUCUUUGGCUUUUGUGUCAAGAUAUGCUGGUCUUACAGUAUGAGUUAAGGAGUAUUCUUUCCUCUUCUGUUUUUUUAAAGAGCUUGAUAAGGACUGACAUUAAUUUUUCUUGAAUGGUAGAAUUCGCCAGUGAAGCCAUCUAGUCCUGGGCUUUUUAUUUCUAUAAGCCCACAUAUGACAGUGGACAUAGAGGACAACGCAGAUAUAGAACAUUUCUUUUAUCACAAUGUACAUUGAAGAUGUCAGUUUCUACAUGUGGGAAGUAGACAUUGAAGGCUUUAUGGUUUACAGACAAGAUCUUUAGAAGAUAAGCACUAAAGGACCAAGGAAAUAAAUACCAGAAAUCAAGAAGAGCACACACUAUUUUCCUUCAUCAAUCCAUAGAACCCUAAUGCUUCUUUAGUUCCAUCAAACACAGAGGAAUGACCACCAUGGCAGAUGGCAACAGAGGAUGUCAACAAUUUUUUGGAGAGAGAAGAGGUACUCCCUUAUAGGGACUCGUAAAGACAUAGAGCAUCUGGAAAUUAACUGCCUCCAUUACACUGCUGAGUCACACACAACGCUUGUUAUGUUUUCAUCACUUCUCUCCAGAAGGCUACAUUAUUGGAAUUUUGAAGUCAUGAAAACAUCAGAUGAACCAACCUGCAACACCUUGGAUUCAGAUUGGAAGAUAAAGAGAAAGUUUAAAGAAUGUGGCCUAUAAAGGCGGGUACCUGGAAAUAUUAACCGACUCACACUGUAAAAAUGAGACCAGUUUCUAAACAAUAGAGAUUGUCUUAGUACAACAUCAAGGUUCAAGACAAAUGUUGAACUAAAAACUUUACACUCCCCACCCCCACUUCAGACAGGUACCAGCAUUGGUGAAUUAUGAUUUUCCUUAGUCAGAAGCACUCAUUUUUACCCAUGUAGACCAUCCUUAGGAAUUAAAUAUUGGUUAUUUAAUGUAGAUUAUAAUGGGAAGCUGAUUUUUUUCACAAUGGCAUAUUUCAAGGACUUGGUUCCAAACUGAGCUGAAGCUUCCCAAUGCGUUUUGUACAGUCUGGGAAAAACUGUGCUGCACUGGCCCACUUUUGAAGGCCAUCAUGCUCUGUAAUAUAAGGAUAUCAUCUUAUUGCUGAUAUCUUUGGAGAGUCCCUAGCAGACACAGAAAAUGAAUGGAGGCAAAGAGUGUGACGGAGGGGACAAGGAAGGAGGUCUUCCAGCUAUACAAGUUCCUGUGGGUUGGCAGCGUCGUGUGGAUCAAAAUGGAGUGCUUUAUGUCAGUCCCAGUGGGUCUUUGUUAUCUUGCUUGGAGCAGGUUAAAACAUACCUGCUUACUGAUGGAACAUGCAAGUGUGGCUUGGAAUGUCCUCUUAUUCUUCCCAAGGUAUUUAAUUUUGAUCCUGGAGCUGCUGUGAAACAGAGAACCGCAGAAGAUGUUAAGGCAGAUGAAGAUGUCACAAAGCUAUGCAUACAUAAAAGAAAAAUUAUUGCAGUGGCCACACUUCAUAAAAGCAUGGAAGCCCCACAUCCUUCUCUGGUGCUCACCAGUCCCGGAGGAGGAACAAAUGCAACUCCAGUAGUACCUUCUCGGGCAGCAACUCCAAGAUCAGUAAGAAAUAAGUCUCAUGAAGGAAUUACAAAUUCUGUAAUGCCUGAAUGUAAGAAUCCUUUCAAGUUAAUGAUUGGAUCAUCAAAUGCCAUGGGAAGGCUAUAUGUACAAGAACUGCCUGGAAGCCAACAACAAGAACUCCACCCUGUCUACCCCCGACAGAGAUUGGGCAGCAGUGAACAUGGACAGAAAUCUCCAUUCCGUGGCAGCCAUGGAGGCCUGCCCAGCCCAGCGUCAUCAGGUUCCCAGAUAUAUGGAGAUGGUUCAAUCUCUCCAAGGACUGACCCACUUGGAAGUCCUGAUGUUUUCACAAGAAGUAAUCCUGGUUUUCAUGGAGCUCCCAAUUCUAGUCCUAUUCACCUGAAUAGGACUCCUCUUUCUCCACCUUCAGUAAUGCUACAUGGUUCUCCUGUACAGUCAUCCUGUGCAAUGGCUGGAAGGACUAAUAUACCUCUUUCCCCAACCUUGACUACAAAGAGUCCAGUAAUGAAAAAACCAAUGUGUAAUUUUUCAACUAAUAUGGAAAUACCACGAGCAAUGUUCCACCACAAACCACCCCAAGGCCCACCUCCCCCUCCUCCACCUUCUUGUGCUCUUCAGAAAAAGCCAUUAACAUCUGAGAAAGAUCCACUUGGCAUUCUUGACCCUAUUCCUAGUAAACCAGUGAAUCAGAACCCUGUUAUCAUUAAUCCAACCAGUUUCCAUUCAAAUGUCCACUCUCAGGUACCUAUGAUGAAUGUAAGCAUGCCUCCUGCUGUUGUUCCUUUGCCAAGUAAUCUCCCAUUGCCAACUGUAAAACCUGGUCACAUGAAUCAUGGGAGUCAUGUACAAAGAGUUCAGCAUUCAGCUUCAACCUCCCUGUCCCCUUCUCCAGUGACAUCCCCCGUGCACAUGAUGGGGACUGGAAUUGGAAGGAUUGAGGCAUCGCCCCAAAGAUCACGCUCAUCUUCCACAUCAUCAGAUCAUGGAAAUUUCAUGAUGCCACCUGUAGGACCCCAGGCCACUUCUAGUGGUAUUAAGGUUCCACCCAGGUCACCAAGGUCAACAAUAGGGUCCCCAAGGCCAUCAAUGCCAUCAAGCCCUUCUACCAAGUCCGAUGGACAUCAUCAGUACAAGGAUAUCCCUAACCCAUUAAUUGCUGGAAUAAGUAAUGUACUAAAUACCCCAAGCAGUGCAGCUUUUCCUACUGCAUCUGCCGGAAGUAGUUCUGUAAAGAGUCAGCCUGGUUUGCUGGGAAUGCCUUUAAAUCAGAUCUUGAACCAGCACAAUGCUGCCUCCUUUCCAGCAAGUAGUUUACUCUCAGCAGCAGCCAAAGCACAGCUAGCAAAUCAAAACAAACUUGCUGGUAACAACAGUAGCAGCAGUAGCAAUUCUGGAGCUGUUGCCGGCAGUGGCAACACUGAAGGACAUAGCACUUUAAACACCAUGUUCCCUCCUACUGCCAACAUGCUUCUCCCAACAGGUGAAGGGCAAAGUGGUCGAGCAGCACUAAGAGAUAAGCUGAUGUCUCAGCAAAAAGACGCAUUGCGGAAAAGAAAACAACCACCUACGACAGUGUUGAGUUUGCUCAGACAGUCUCAAAUGGAUAGUUCUGCAGUUCCUAAACCUGGACCUGACUUGCUAAGGAAGCAGGGUCAGGGUUCAUUUCCCAUCAGUUCAAUGUCUCAGUUACUACAGUCUAUGAGUUGUCAAAGCUCUCACUUGAGUAGCAAUAGUACCCCGGGUUGUGGGGCCUCAAAUACUGCUUUGCCUUGCUCUGCUAACCAGCUGCAUUUUACAGAUCCCAGUAUGAACUCUAGUGUUCUUCAGAACAUACCUUUAAGAGGGGAAGCCGUGCACUGCCACAAUGCAAACACUAACUUUGUUCACAGUAACAGUCCAGUCCCCAACCACCAUCUUGCAGGUUUAAUAAAUCAGAUUCAGGCUAGCGGGAACUGUGGGAUGCUCAGUCAGUCGGGCAUGGCUUUAGGAAAUUCCUUACAUCCCAAUCCACCUCAGUCAAGAAUUUCAACGUCCUCCACUCCAGUGAUACCAAACAGCAUUGUUAGCAGCUAUAAUCAAACAAGUUCUGAAGCAGGCGGUUCAGGACCAUCAUCCUCCAUAGCCAUAGCGGGCACCAACCACCCUGCCAUCACAAAGACAACAUCUGUUCUUCAAGAUGGCGUCAUAGUCACCACUGCAGCUGGAAACCCACUGCAGAGUCAGCUACCCAUUGGGAGUGAUUUUCCUUUUGUUGGCCAGGAGCACGCACUUCAUUUUCCAUCCAACAGCACUUCAAACAACCAUCUUCCACACCCCUUGAACCCCAGCCUCCUCAGUUCUCUACCUAUCUCUUUGCCAGUGAAUCAACAGCAUCUCCUAAACCAGAAUCUAUUAAAUAUCCUCCAGCCUUCAGCAGGAGAAGGCAAGUCUGAGAUCAACCUCCACCCUUUAGGUUUUCUCAACCCGAAUGUAAACGCUGCUUUAGCUUUUCUCUCCAGUGACAUGGAUGGGCAGGUAUUGCAGCCUGUUCACUUUCAGCUCUUAGCAGCCUUGCUUCAGAACCAAGCCCAAGCAGCUGCCAUGCUUCCCCUGCCAUCUUUCAAUCUGACCAUCUCAGAUCUUUUGCAACAGCAAAAUACCCCUUUACCCUCAUUAACACAGAUGACAGCCCCACCAGACCAUUUGCCAAGCAAUCAGUCAGACAACAGCCGAGCUGAGACCCUUUUAACCAGCCCCCUGGGGAACCCUUUACCAAGCUUUGCAGGCAGUGACACUACUUUUAACCCCCUGUUCCUCCCAGCUGUCAAUGGGGCCUCAGGAUUAAUGACCUUGAAUCCCCAGCUGUUGGGAGGUGUCCUGAACUCGGCAUCGGCCAACACCGCUAAUCAUCCAGAGGUUUCCAUAGCAACCUCCUCCCAGGCAACCACUACCACAACCACUACAUCAUCAGCAGUGGCAGCACUGACUGUCUCAACACUUGGUGGGACAGCAGUGGUGUCAAUGGCAGAAACAUUGCUGAAUAUAUCUAAUAAUGCUGGGAAUACACCUGGUCCAGCUAAACUCAACAGUAACUCUGUGGUGCCACAGCUACUUAACCCUCUACUGGGGACAGGUCUACUUGGUGAUAUGUCAUCAAUAAACAAUACUUUGAGUAACCAUCAACUGACUCAUCUACAGUCGCUGUUAAACAACAAUCAGAUGUUUCCUCCAAAUCAGCAACAGCAGCAACUUCUCCAGGGGUACCAGAAUCUCCAGGCGUUCCAAGGACAGUCCACAAUUCCUUGCCCAGCUAACAAUAACCCCAUGGCUUGUCUGUUUCAGAACUUUCAGGUGAGAAUGCAGGAAGAUGCAGCUCUCCUAAACAAAAGAAUAAGCACUCAGCCUGGGCUCACAGCACUUCCUGAGAAUCCAAACACUACACUUCCACCUUUUCAAGAUACACCUUGUGAGUUGCAACCGAGGAUUGACCCAUCUCUUGGUCAACAGGUGAAGGAUGGCCUCGUUGUGGGUGGCCCAGGUGAUGCUUCCGUAGAUGCCAUUUACAAAGCAGUUGUCGAUGCAGCCAGCAAAGGAAUGCAGGUUGUCAUCACCACUGCAGUCAACAGUACAACUCAGAUCAGCCCCAUUCCAGCUCUGAGUGCCAUGAGUGCCUUCACUGCCUCAAUUGGUGACCCAUUAAAUCUCUCCAGUGCUGUCAGUGCGGUCAUUCAUGGACGGAACAUGGGAGGUGUUGAUCAUGAUGGUAGGCUGAGGAAUUCAAGAGGGGCUCGGCUGCCCAAGAAUCUAGACCAUGGGAAAAAUGUGAACGAAGGAGAUGGGUUUGAAUAUUUCAAGUCAGCAAGUUGCCACACAUCCAAAAAACAGUGGGACGGGGAGCAAAGCCCCAGAGGGGAGCGAAACAGGUGGAAGUACGAGGAAUUUUUAGAUCAUCCAGGCCAUAUCCACAGUAGUCCUUGUCAUGAAAGGCCCAACAAUGUCUCUACACUGCCAUUUCUGCCUGGGGAACAGCACCCAAUACUGUUACCACCAAGAAACUGUCCAGGGGAUAAAAUUCUAGAGGAAAAUUUCAGGUAUAAUAACUACAAAAGAACUAUGAUGAGUUUUAAGGAGAGACUAGAGAACACUGUGGAAAGAUGUGCACACAUAAAUGGGAAUAGACCUCGACAGAGUCGGGGAUUUGGAGAGCUGCUAAGCACUGCAAAGCAAGACCUGGUCCUAGAGGAGCAGUCUCCAAGUUCCUCAAAUAGUUUGGAAAAUUCUCUGGUCAAAGACUACAUCCAUUACAAUGGAGACUUUAAUGCCAAAAGCGUUAAUGGGUGUGUGCCUAGCCCUUCAGAUGCUAAAAGCAUUAGUAGUGAAGAUGACCUAAGGAACCCAGACUCCCCCUCUUCAAAUGAAUUGAUACAUUAUAGACCAAGGACGUUCAAUGUUGGCGACUUGGUCUGGGGCCAAAUCAAAGGACUGACUUCCUGGCCUGGAAAAUUAGUAAGAGAAGACGACGUUCACAAUUCAUGUCAACAAAGCCCCGAGGAAGGGAAGGUCUGGGUAAUGUGGUUUGGUCUUCAUACCUUCACUCAGGUGGAGCCCGAGAAGUUGAAGACACUAACAGAAGGUUUGGAAGCCUACAGCCGUGUCCGGAAAAGGAACAGAAAAAGUGGAAAGCUAAAUAACCAUUUAGAAGCUGCUAUUCAUGAGGCCAUGAGUGAACUGGACAAAAUGUCUGGGACUGUACACCAAAUCCCACAGGGUGACAGACAAAUGAGACCCCCCAAACCCAAGAGGAGGAAGAUCUCCAGAUAACAGAGACUACUCCACUAAUGCGCAGUGUUUAUUAAAGGAACAUGCACAGAUGUAUCUGUAUAUAGGUAUUGAUAUAGCCACAGUUAUAUCAAUAUUUAGACUAUGGCAGAUAGCUACCACCACCACAGGGUGCUAAAAGAAACAGUGAUACAAAAUUUUUUUGAUCAGGAAGGAUAAUGAAUGCUGGAAAAGCCAAUCAAAGUCUCUGUGUGAUGAGAGUGAUCAAUGGUCAAGAGAUUACUGAGAAACUCUUUUUCUAUAAUACUAAAUUGUGAUUAUAAGAAAUAGUCCAAAUGUUUCUGAAGAAUUUUCAAUGUUGUAUAUAGAAAAUACAGAAUUUCAUGGUGAUAUCAGAAAUGUAAAUAUUGUACAGUAUUGUCAUGUACAAGCGUACCUAAUGCACACUUUAUCUUUUAUUGUACAAAGAAAUAGUGUACAAAAUUCUUUGGUUUCUAUGGAGUACACCUACCAGAGACUACCAGUGUAAAGUGAUAAAUAAAAAUACAACCUAAAUGCUUUUCUAUGAUAAUGUAAAAGAUGCUGUUUUUGUAUUUAACAGCAGAGAAAAGGCAUGAUGAUGUAAUAUCUGAAUUAUGACAUACACUGCACACCACUGAGUGUCCAUUUAUAUUGUCUGUUUGGAAUGAACCUUGCCUGGAAGCACUGGACUCAAUUUCGGGUGUCUAGGAAAUUGCAACUUUGCAGAUUUCUAAAGGGAUGAGGGCUCACAGGUCUAAAUUAAGAAUUCAGAAACUGCAACCAUUUGUUGCAUAUUUUUUUUACCUAAGUUUUAAAAUAGAAUAGGUUUUAUAAAAAAAAAUCUUAGAUGGAAUAUUUUACUCAGCCAUUUCUGUAGUUAACAUUUGAUAGCCACCUGUUGAAGCAGAUAGCUUAUACUGACUGCACCACCGCUGGUGCUCAGAAUUGAGGGUUUUUUUGCAAAUGAUAUCUGACAAGGUAAAACUUUCUAUUUCCGUACAUGGAGGCAAAAACCCCACUUUGCAACCAUUAUCAGAGGUAAGAUUGAUAAUAAUUCAUUUUUUUGUAGUGGCAAAUAUAAAUAUGAAUCAUCAAAGCAAGUUUCAUAUCCAUUCAUCAGUAUUACUUAACCCAGAAGUUAAGGUGGCUUACGGAAUUAUUAGCAAUGGUAAUUUUUUUAUCAGUAUUGUGUAACAUAUCAGAUUUAUUUUAUUUAAAGAAUUAUUUAUACCAUUAACAGAUUCUUAUAUAUAUUAAUGUGGCAAAAAUGUGCAGGUUAAAUCUAUUAACCAAAUUAUUUAUAUUAUAUUAAGUAAGAAAAAAUGUGAAACAAAUGUAGAGAGAAAAUACUACAUUACAAGUAUACAAACCUAAAACUGUGAGCCAUUGUAAAGUACAAGGUAAUUAAUAAGAAAUGUAGCACAACAUAAUUUUCCGUCUUCUUCUCACAAUUUUUGUGGUGGUGGUAUUACCCUAUCUUCCAGGCAGUUAAGCAAAGUUUAGGCUUCCAGCCUGACUUCAGUUGAUGGAUUGUCAAAAGAAGGGAUCUAUUAUCCCUUUAUUCUUGGAACCACCAGUCCCUGCCCCAAACCCUUAAACCCCUAGAGAGCACUGCCUCGUCCUCUAGCCUGGGGCUCACACAACAGUCUGCCACUCAGGCUGCUAGGAGAUUCUCCAAUAGCAGGCUCAGCACCUCAAACUGCCCACCACCUCUCCUACUGCUCCUCUCCCACCCACCACCCAAACUCCUCAGUCCUGUCAUGUAGCAGAGUUCCAGUAACUCAGGAAAAUGGAGACCAAGGUCAUUCCUUAAGUUGGUUUCUUGGGGCCACAGCACAGAGCAUGCCACCUGGGCUCACUUUUGAUAGCAACAGCUCUUAGUUAUUCCCCUAGGUCUCCUGUGUCUCUCUGUCCCUCUGUUCCUACUUUCAACCUACCCCCAAGCCUGAUGGAAUGCAACUGGCUACCCUGGGCUUCAUGACCUCAAAGUAGGAACCCUUCGUUCUGGGGGUAGGUUCAUUUUGUCUCUCUUGUAAUGGUGGGAUUGCCUGCCCAGUUCCUUCAUGCAGUCACAUGAAGUAAUCUUUUGUGUAGUUUAGUUGACACAUGUUUAUAAGUUAAAAGUUGAUGUGGCUAGUAUGUUUAAACCAUUAAUGUCCAUUUUUUUUGCACCAACCUGUUUUUCUACUGUUUUUUCCUACACAUUUUUGUUUAUUCACAGACAGACAGACAUGUGUGUUUGUAUGCUGGGUGUGUCUGUAUGUGUGUAUGUGUUGAUAUGUAAAUUUUUUAGCCUUUGCUUUUCUGUCUUCAGGCUGAGUUUGUGUUGACCAAGCCUUCUUUUUGGUAUUUUGAGCUAAUUCAGUUUGUGCUUCCCUCCCAUUGUAUACUUUACAUAAGUAGACCAUGUAAAGUAUGUUUGUGCCCAUGAUUUCACUGGUUGCUAUGGCUUUGAUAUGGGUGCUAGGUGUAGUAGUUUCAGUCCACGUGGGUUUUUUUCAUCUCUCUUAGAGUUAUAUGGUUUUGUGUAAGCAGUUAAUGUAAAUAUUGUUAGCAUUACAGGUCAUACAGUGCUGUAACAUUUUUUUAAAUGUUGCACCUACUUUACAAUUAAAAAAUUGGUCACUCGCACUUCAAUUUUGCCCAUAGAGCCAUUUCUUUGUCUUUGUAUUGAAGCCAAUUCAUUUUUUUAAAUGAAGGCUAGGCCUUCUAUGUUACCAAAAUUUUUAUUCCCUAAAAUAAACUUUUUAAGAAACAAAUCCAAGAAUGGAAACAGAUGAAAAAUUUUUUCUUCUUUAAAGAACAUAAUAGUUCCUGCUGGAAAAGGAAAUCUAAUUUUAUUUUGUGUCCCUUAACAGUCCUAGGAAGCACAAGGAGAAUAAACUAAACCUCUAAGAAGGUUUUAAAAAUUAUUUCAAAUGAGUGAAAAUUAACUGAGCAGCUUUUGUGUGAUUUGUCUUGUUUGUAGCAUUAAAAGCAAACCAGGGUUUUUAUUUAUUUAAAGGAACAUUUUUGGCUUGUACUUUUCAGUGCCAUUAUGAAUGAAAAUGUUUUAAGAACAUUCAUCCCUUGUGAUAUCAUGGGCCACUUUUAGUCUUUUAUUUGGACCCUGACUUUGAGUUUUUGCUAUGCCUGUUUUUUAAGUAAACACAGCCUUCUUAUUUGAACGUAACACUGCAGAAUUGCAGGAAGAGAAAAGGGCAGUUAGUUAUUUCACUUUCUGUAAGUUUUAGGAAGAUUCUUAUAUCCUACGAGGUGACUCAUGUUUCAUUUUAGACCAUGAUAGCACAUUGUUGUUAACUUUGGUAAUCUUCCAUGCAGUUUGCAGUGUUCCCUUGCAAGUCACAAGCAUAUAUGCAUUAAGAUUUUAAAAUCUAAGAUGCUUAAGAUGUUGGUGGCAUUGCUCUUUCUGAAAAGAAAGACAAAAUACUAGACCUUGCUGAAAAUUGGAUAUCUUAUUUACUUUGCCCAUUUAUGCCCGAAUGGUGUAAUGCAAGACUCAAGACUUUUCAAUGUAGUAUAUCAAAUGAGUUGUGCAUUGAUUCAUUUGGGGGACAUGAACAAAAAUUAUCAACCAGCCAGAACUGUAAUAUUUAAUUAGUUCAUCUUUUUCUUUCAUUCACUCUAUCACAUUUGCAUUAGCCAAAGAGAUAAGAACAUUAGUAAUUCAUAUGUGUAAACAACCCAGAAGUGAAUAUUAAAUCAGUGAGCCAAAAAGCAAUAAACAACUCGAGCAUGGGAAAUCCUGCUAACAGUGGGGAGUCUGAUAUAGAAAAAAUAUAUAAAAAGCAUUAUCUUCAAAUAUGAAAGAUUAAUUUGUAUCUACUGUAAAUAUGUAUUACCAGCCUUAUCUGCAUUUAUACACACUGUGUGUGUACCUCAGUGACCUUUUAUAAACCGGAAAAAUGGUUGAUUUAAUAAUUUGUUAUGUAAAUACAAAGUUGUCUAUAAAUUGGAAAAUUUGAUGCCAGAUGGCUUCAUAAUAUACAAAUGUGUUUUGUAACAUCAUGCCUUUAUGGAUUAAGUAUAAAUACACUGGAUUGUCUAUGUA